GCACUGCCAUCUCCCCACACCCUCCAGGAAGUUCAGGUCGCCAUCAUAAACAACUCUAUGUGCAACCACCUCUUCCUCAAGUACAGUUUCCGCAAGGACAUCUUUGGAGACAUGGUUUGUGCUGGCAAUGCCCAAGGCGGGAAGGAUGCCUGCUUCGGUGACUCAGGUGGACCCUUGGCCUGUAACAAGAAUGGACUGUGGUAUCAGAUUGGAGUCGUGAGCUGGGGAGUGGGCUGUGGUCGGCCCAAUCGGCCCGGUGUCUACACCAAUAUCAGCCACCACUUUGAGUGGAUCCAGAAGCUGAUGGCCCAGAGUGGCAUGUCCCAGCCAGACCCCUCCUGGCCGCUACUCUUUUUCCCUCUUCUCUGGGCUCUCCCACUCCUGGGGCCGGUCUGAGCCUACCUGAGCCCAUGCAGCCUGGGGCCACUGCCAAGUCAGGCCCUGGUUCUCUUCUGUCUUGUUUGGUAAUAAACACAUUCCAGUUGAUGCCUUGCAGGGCAUUCUUCAAAA